AGACGGCCAAUGGCGGCGGUGCUCGGGGCGCUCGGGGCGACGCGGCGCUUGUUGGCGGCGCUGCGAGGCCAGAGCCUAGGGCUAGCGGCCAUGUCAUCAGGUACUCACAGGUUGACUGCAGAGGAGAGGAACCAAGCUAUACUUGACCUUAAAGCAGCAGGAUGGUCGGAAUUAAGUGAGAGAGAUGCCAUCUACAAAGAAUUCUCCUUCCACAAUUUUAAUCAGGCAUUUGGCUUUAUGUCCCGAGUUGCCCUACAAGCAGAGAAGAUGAAUCAUCACCCAGAAUGGUUCAAUGUAUACAACAAGGUCCAGAUAACUCUCACCUCACAUGACUGUGGUGAACUGACCAAAAAAGAUGUGAAGCUGGCCAAGUUUAUUGAAAAAGCAGCUGCUUCUGUGUGAUUUCUUCCAAAAUACAUGUAAAAUCUUGUACACAUCUUAGCUGCAAUGUAUGUUGAAGGAAAUUUAUGUGAACAAAUAGAGUUGUUCUUUUUCUCUUUUUUUUAAGACAGAGUGUUGCUCUGUCGCCCAGGCCAGAGUGCAGUGGUAUGAUCUCGGCUCACUGUAACCUCCGCCUCCCAGGUUCAGGUGAUUCUCCUGCCUCAGCCUCCUGAGUAGCUGGGAUUACAAGCACGUGUCACCACGCCUGGCUAAUUUUUGUAUUUUUAGUAUAGACAGGGUUUUACCACGUUGGUCAGGCUGGUCUCGAACUCCUGACCUCGUGAUCCGCCUGCCUCAGCCUCCCAAAGUGCUGGGAUUACAGGCAUGAGCCACCAUGCCUGGCUGUUGAAUUGUUCUUAAGGCAUCAUAUCUAGAAGCAAAGAAAAAAGAAAAAUAACAAUUUAAGUUGUGUAAAUUGUUUGCCUUUAUAUAUUACAUUUGGUAAAAUCAGUGCUUAAAUACGCAAUGAUUUAAACUGGAACCUGAGGUAUUUUUCAUGCUAUCUAAUCAUAUACCUAAGAUAAACCAACCCAGUUACUUAUAUUAAUAAUAUUCAGAAAGAGAAGUGGCUUUUUUUUUUUUUUGAGACGGAGUCUUGCUCUGUCACCAGGCUGGAGUGCAGUGGCGGGAUCUCGGCUCACUGCAACCUCUGCCUCCCAGGUUCAAAUGAUUCUCCUGCCACAGCCUCCCGAGUAGCUGGGACUAUAGGCACGUGCCACUGCGCCUAGCUAAUUUUUGUAUUUUUAGUAGAGAUGGGGUUUCAUUAUGUUGGCCAGGAUGGUCUCGAUCUACUGACCUCGUGAUCCACCUGCCUCCACCUCCGAAAGUGUUGGGAUCACAGGCAUGAGCCACCGCGCUUGGCCAGAAGUGGCAUUCUUAAAUUCAAGAAAUUGGGAUGGGGAGUAUUCACACAUUUUAUAACCCAGAAAUUCAAGCAAUUCUGGUGACUACAAAUGCAUUGUUUUGGAGAAUAGUUGUAAGGUGGAAAAAGAAUUAGGAACUCGACAGAUAGUGAGUUUUAACUUUAAAUAACAAUUCUUCUUUUGUUUUGUUUUGUUUGAGACGGGGUCUCGCUCUGCUGCCCAGGCUGGAGUGCAGUGGCAGGAUCACGGUUUAUUGCAGCCUUAACCUCCUGGGCUCAAGCAGUUCUCCCUCCUCAGCCUCCAGAGUAGCUGGGACUAUAGGCAAGUGCCACCACGCCUGACUAAUUUUUAAAUUUUUUGUAGAGAUGGGGUCUCCCAUCUUGCCCAGGCUGGCCUUGAACUCUUGGGCUCAAGCAAGCCUCCCACCUCUGCCUCCCAAAGUCCAAGGAUUACAGGUGUGAGCCAUUGCCCCCAGCCAGUAUAACAGUUUGUGUGUGUGUGUGUGUGUGUGUGUGUGUGUGUGUUUGACACGGGGUCUCAUUCUGUUGCCCAGGCAGUAGUGUAGUGGUGCGACCAUGGCUCACUGUAGUCUUGACUUCUCAGGCUCAAGUGAUCCUCUCACCUCAGCCUCCUGAGUAGCAGCGGUUACAGGCAUGCAUCACCACACCUGGCUUAUUUUUAAAACUUUUUUGUGGAGACAGGGUCUUACUAUGUUGCCAUGGCUGGUCUAGAACUUCUGGGCUCGAGUAAUCCUCCUGCCUUGGCCUCUCAAAAUGUUGGGAUUACAGGUGUGAGCCACUGUGUCAUAACAAUUAUUUUAAAAUUUUUAUUUAUUUAUUUUUAAUAAUUAUACAAGAUGGAGUCUCACUAUGUUGCCCAGGCUGGUCUUGAAUGCCUGGGCUCAAAUGAUCUUCCUGCCUUGACCCCCCAAAGUGCUGGGAUUACAGGCGUGAGCCACUGCGCCUGGCCUAUAACAAUUCUUAUGAAGCUAAAGUUGAUUUGGAUUUUAGCUGCCGUUACUACUUAUAUAAUUAAUUAGAUUAAACAAGUCACAAAAAUUG